AAACCGUGUCUCACUCUGUCGCCCAGGCUGGAGGAGUGCAGUGGUGUGAUCUCAGCUCACUGCAACCUCCACCUCCCAGGUUCAAGCAAUUCUUCUGCCUCAGCCUCCCAAGUAGCUGGGAUUACAGGUGCCUGCCACCAUGCCUGGCUAAUUUUUUUGUAUUUUUAGUAGAAACAGGGUGUCACCAUGUUGGCCAGACUGGUCUCAAACUCCUGACCUCAAGUGAUCCACCUGCCUCAGCCUCCCAAAGUGCUGGGAUUAUAGUCGUGAGCCACCACGCCUGGCCAGAGUUUUUUAUUUUUAUCACCACCAUAGAUGUUACAGUUGGCUGUGGUCACAAAAGUAGUUAAUUGUGUCAGCACCCAAAUAAACAUCUAACAGGUUUCUCAACAGAGGAAUCCACAGUCCAAUUCCACUUCAAUUGAUAGACCCAAAAAAUAUAAUUUAAUCAAAGUUCUAGAGUUUUUGUUUGUUUGUUUGAGAUGGAGUCUUGCUCUGUCGCCCAGGCUGGAACGCAGUGGUGACAUCUCGGCUCACUGCAACCUCCACCUCCCAGGUUCAAGUGAUUCUCCUGCCUCAGCCUCCUGAGUAGCUGGGACUACAGGCGCCUGCCACCACGCCCAGCUAAUUUUUGUAUUUUUAGUAGAGAUGGGGUUUCACCAUGUUGGCCAGGAUGGUCUUGAUCUCUUGACCUCGUGAUCUGCCUGCCUCGGCCUCCCAAAGUGCUGGCAUUACAGGCAUGAGCCACCAUGCCUGGCCCAAAGUUCUAGAAUUUUUUAAAGGUAUUCAUGGUGACUCAGGAAUACACACAUACACACACACACACACACACACACACACACACAUACACACAUAUAAUUUGAAAGAGGUGAGUAUGUACUCUGACUUCAGCUCUCAGGUUUUAAAAAUUAUAUUAGUGGGACCAGUUAUGACAAGAAUAAUCAUUAUAGUACUUUUCAGAUUUUAUAACCUGGAGCAGAUUAUUUUAAGUUGAUUAGUAGGUUCUGUUACAGUUUUUCUUUUGAUCGUGCACUUAUAGUCUUCAUUUAAUUCCUCAUAGAAUCCCAGUCACCUUUAUAUAUCAUAUUAUUGGAAGAGAUUCAUCUUCAUAAUCUCCAGUUUUUUCACAGUGCCUCACAGAGUUAAUCAUGCCUUUUGGAGCUAGAAGGACUUUAGAACUUAUCUAGUUAUGCUCCUUUAUAUUAUAAGUAAGGGAAUAGAAUCAAUAAGACAGUUUCUGCCCAAAGUCAUGUUACCAGUUGGUGACAGAGCUGGAAAUACGUAGAGAUCUAUACCCUUAAAUCUCUCCACUCACAUGCUGAUAUACUUUCUACUACAAUAUGCUAUAGCUUUAUGGAACUCAGGGUGAUGAUCAGACGUGUCAUUAGAACAUGAGUCCUCUGCUUCUGAUUCAGGCAUACUUUUGGGAUUCUUCCAUCUUUAAAGGAAAAAGGAAGCCAUUCAUCUAUAUUUAGUAACCCAGUAAUAUCUCACUUAGUUUAGGGUUAGAUCUUUAGUUAAUUCAACCUUAUAGAUCAUACUUAUGAAGGUGAUAACUGACACGUGUUCACUGAAUUUUAAUUUGAUAGGCAAUACAUCUACCCACUCCAUUAUUUUUUAAAACUUCAUUUAAUAGUUUAAACAAGAUUGGUUUUGUUUUCAAUUUUUAUUCACUCUUCAUAGAAUCACAAUUACCUUUAUAUAUCAUAUGUUAUUGGAAGAGAUUCCUCAGUAAUCUCCAAUCUCUCAUAGUGCCUCACAGGGUUGGUCAAUGGCUUUUGGAACUGGAAGGACCUUAGAACUUAUCUGUUAUGCUCCUGAUAGCCAAUAGCAGAUAGAAGCUUGCAAUCAAGAGGGUAGGACAUGUGUUCUUCAAUGGAUAUCAAAGGAAGAGGUUGCAAACCAAAGCCAUUUGGCAAGCCCUGUAGCCUGGGCCAUUUAAGACAGGGGCGGUCUCAGCCAAAUUGCACCCAUUUAACUAUCCCAAAGAGCCACAGUGCCUACAACCCAGGCCCUAAGUUGAUGAAGAAAAAGUCAAGGAAGGAGGUGAUACAAUUGGAAAUAUUCCCAUCAAAUGGUUAAUCUUAUUUAGAAAAUGGGCAUAUUAGAAAAAGUCCUUCCAAGAUGAUUUUGGAUAAUAAAAGUUGUAUUUGUGGAAAUUGGUAUUAUCUCUGUUUUAUGCACUUACAUUUAUCCCUUACAUUUUGUUUUUAGUGACCCUACAUGACAUUAAAUUUAAAGUAAAACAUUGUUUAAUGUUACCUUUUGGCUUGAGAAUGUCUUUCAGCUCCAGAAUUAUUGUUACUCAUAUUUUAAUCAGUAAGUCAUUUAAGCUAUGACAGAGUAGGAAUUGAGAAAUUAUUUCAUAUGCUACAGUAUUGAAAUGUGGAUGCUGCCUUGUUUUAUAAGAAGAUGAUCAAGGUUUGUGUGCCCAUUACCUUUCCUCUGCCUGAAAGACGUGUCUCAAGAAAAAUAAAUUCUAUUUUAGAUGCAGGUACUGCAUUUUAUUCUAAGAAUUGAUAUCAAUUCAAAACAUAGAAAACUGUAAAAGAUAAAUCAGGAGAUGGCUGAUUCAUAAUGGGUAAUAAAAUAAAUAGCACUUUCGAGCUGAUGUCGUCAGUGACUCUUGGAUUUUCUAACAAAAGGUUCCUUUACUGUUGUCAUAGAGAGAUUGUGAAUUUCUCUGACUCUGAAGAAUCAACUAGAAGAAGUAGAAUCACCAGAACAUUUUGCUCAGCUGAAAGCACAAAGUAAACUCAGUUACUGGGAAUCAGCAAAAACCACAGGCAUCACUGGUCCCAGGGAUUUAGAGUCCAGAAACCUCUCCAGGUGAUGGACUGUUGAUUUGGGGCUCUAUGCAUUGUCACAGACAGCUGGGGAUAUCAGUUUCUGGACCAAAUGACCCAAUAAGAGAUGCUGGUCGUAAAAAUCCAUUUUUAUCUGGAAUGUUUCUAGAAGAUCAAAACCUUUUUCCUUCCAGCAUCUAAUGCCUGAGUGAUACAUUUAAAAAUUUUUAGUCUGCGUGGGCACCCUCUUUUUCUAGGAGCAGCACUUUUUAUUUUUGAAAUUAUCCUACAAUGAAUUACCGGCUUUUCUUCUGUUCUCAUCUUUUUCCUUCCCCAGCAUACACACACUGUAAAUAUGUGCCAUAUUCUUAGGCAAUCCCACUUUCUCAACCUUUGUUGAGUGACCCAAGCAAGGUUAAAUUCGAGUUCUCCCCAACGAGUUUUCCCAGCUGCAAUUGAAGAAGAGAUACAGUCCAUCUCUGUGGUGGAAACUCCAGGUUGUGAAACUCAAGAUCAAUCAGCAAUAGAACCUCUGGAGCAGCUGCUGGGUGAUGAGAAGAAGCAGGCAGAAGAAAUGGACAGAAUCCUGGAGGAACCUGAGUCCCACAUGGCAGCCAGUGUUGGUUUAUUAUUACCAAAAGCAAUGCUGUUCUGGAAAGGCAAGGACUGCAGUGUCUCAUAUGAUGCAAUUGGACGGAACCUCAAGACGACAUUUGCUCCCAGCAAAGGGCAUUCAGCAGAACAAGGACCAAUCAGAAUUCAUCCAACAAUCAUUUUCAGUGUCAUCUAAGACUGGCAGUCUGCCAAGUUCUAUUGAGGGAGCUGGGGAAAGACAGCAAGCAAGCCCCAGUCCUACCAGCAAGGUGUUACAGACAGUGGGCGUCUGAAAAACAACAGAGAAAUGGACAAGGAGGUAACAGAAUGGCAGGGAGUGAGAAGCGUUACGCAGAAAGACAAAGAAUGGUGAAGAGACAGGAGGUGGAAGAGAUGGAAGGUGCCUUUUCAGAUGAGAUGCUUGCUGGAGGAUGGUAUCCUGAGGAGAUGAUGUUUGAGCAGUGGUCUGAUUGAAAAUGAUUUUAUUCAAGCAAGCAACUUAUUUCAUUUCCUUGUUUGCUACAGUUUCCUGUGGAUGUCUGACUCAACUCUAUGAAAACGCCUUCUUCAGAGGUGGGGAUGUAGCUUCCAUGUACACCCCAAAUGCCCAAUACUGCCAGAUGAGGUGCACAUUCCACCCAAGGUGUUUGCUAUUCAGUUUUCUUCCAGCAAGUUCAAUCAAUGACAUGGAGAAAAGGUUUGGUUGCUUCUUGAAAGAUAGUGUUACAGGAACCCUGCCAAAAGUACAUCGAACAGGUGCAGUUUCUGGACAUUCCUUGAAGCAAUGUGGUCAUCAAAUAAGUGCUUGCCAUCGAGACAUUUAUAAAGGAGUUGAUAUGAGAGGAGUCAAUUUUAAUGUGUCUAAGGUUAGCAGUGUUGAAGAAUGCCAAAAAAGGUGCACCAGUAACAUUCGCUGCCAGUUUUUUUCAUAUGCCACGCAAACAUUUCACAAGGCAGAGUACCGGAACAAUUGCCUAUUAAAGUACAGUCCCGGAGGAACACCUACCGCUAUAAAGGUGCUGAGUAACGUGGAAUCUGGAUUCUCACUGAAGCCCUGUGCCCUUUCAGAAAUUGGUUGCCACAUGAACAUCUUCCAGCAUCUUGCGUUCUCAGAUGUGGAUGUUGCCAGGGUUCUCACUCCAGAUGCUUUUGUGUGUCGGACCAUCUGCACCUAUCACCCCAACUGCCUCUUCUUUACAUUCUAUACAAAUGUAUGGAAAAUCGAGUCACAAAGAAAUGUUUGUCUUCUUAAAACAUCUGAAAGUGGCACACCAAGUUCCUCUACUCCUCAAGAAAACACCAUAUCUGGAUAUAGCCUUUUAACCUGCAAAAGAACUUUACCUGAACCCUGCCAUUCUAAAAUUUACCCGGGAGUUGACUUUGGAGGAGAAGAAUUGAAUGUGACUUUUGUUAAAGGAGUGAAUGUUUGCCAAGAGACUUGCACAAAGAUGAUUCGCUGUCAGUUUUUCACUUAUUCUUUACUCCCAGAAGACUGUAAGGAAGAGAAGUGUAAGUGUUUCUUAAGAUUAUCUAUGGAUGGUUCUCCAACUAGGAUUGCGUAUGGGACACAAGGGAGCUCUGGUUACUCUUUGAGAUUGUGUAACACUGGGGACAACUCUGUCUGCACAACAAAAACAAGCACACGCAUUGUUGGAGGAACAAACUCUUCUUGGGGAGAGUGGCCCUGGCAGGUGAGCCUGCAGGUGAAGCUGACAGCUCAGAGGCACCUGUGUGGAGGGUCACUCAUAGGACACCAGUGGGUCCUCACUGCUGCCCACUGCUUUGAUGGGCUUCCCCUGCAGGAUGUUUGGCGCAUCUAUAGUGGCAUUUUAAAUCUGUCAGACAUUACAAAAGAUACACCUUUCUCACAAAUAAAAGAGAUUAUUAUUCACCAAAACUAUAAAGUCUCAGAAGGGAAUCAUGAUAUCGCCUUGAUAAAACUCCAGGCUCCUUUGAAUUACACUGAAUUCCAAAAACCAAUAUGCCUACCUUCCAAAGGUGACACAAGCACAAUUUAUACCAACUGUUGGGUAACCGGAUGGGGCUUCUCGAAGGAGAAAGGUGAAAUCCAAAAUAUUCUACAAAAGGUAAAUAUUCCUUUGGUAACAAAUGAAGAAUGCCAGAAAAGAUAUCAAGAUUAUAAAAUAACCCAACGGAUGGUCUGUGCUGGCUAUAAAGAAGGGGGAAAAGAUGCUUGUAAGGGAGAUUCAGGUGGUCCCUUAGUUUGCAAACACAAUGGAAUGUGGCGUUUGGUGGGCAUCACCAGCUGGGGUGAAGGCUGUGCCCGCAGGGAGCAACCUGGUGUCUACACCAAAGUCGCUGAGUACAUGGACUGGAUUUUAGAGAAAACACAGAGCAGUGAUGGAAAAGCUCAGAUGCAGUCACCAGCAUGAGAAGCAGUCCAGAGUCUAGGCAAUUUUUACAACCUGAGUUCAAGUCAAAUUCUGAGCCUGGGGGGUCCUCAUCUGCAAAGCAUGGAGAGUGGCAUCUUCUUUGCAUCCUAAGGACGAAAAACACAGUGCACUCAGAGCUGCUGAGGACAAUGUCUGGCUGAAGCCCGCUUUCAGCACGCCGUAACCAGGGGCUGACAAUGCGAGGUCGCAACUGAGAUCUCCAUGACUGUGUGUUGUGAAAUAAAAUGGUGAAAGAUCA